UCAGCGUGGGAAGGUUCUCAGUGCCUCCUCUGUGAAAACUGCCUGCAAACUGGGAUCCUCUUUCUUUUAAUGUCUGUGUUGUGUUUCCCAGUGUGAUGUGUCUGCAGAGGUGUUUAUUAAAUAAUUUCAUCAUUUCCAGAGGGAACAGGUCUCUCCCCUGUCAGUCAACUUUGGAGCUAAUGAGCAAUGAGUGUCAGGCUUUUGUGGCUCCAAUUGUAAAUGGGAACAAACUCUCUGAGCCUAAAUGCCAUUUGAACAAAUACAGAUGUGUGGUGUAGGUACUGCACCAAUAGCUGAAUAGGGGCAGUUUUAUUUUUGAAAAGAAUAACCUUUCAAAUGUCAUUUGAUAGCAUUUAUUAUGUAAUUGUCAGGACCAAUUUAUUAUGCAUUUAAUUAGUUGUAAUCUAUGACUUAGUCCAAAGGUGAUUCAGUAUAUGUACCUAAAACUUUUCCUUCCUCUUCACCAAACUACUGGAGUAACCUUACUCUUACUGCAUGACUGAAAUAAGGCUUUCUAUGAGUUUUGCUUGUAGAACAAUCUUUCUUUAUAUCCUGCCUCGGCCUUGCCUCCUUUUUUACUGCCGUGCCUUGCUUGAAUCUUCUAACCCCAGUCCUCCUCCUCAGUUUGACUUGAACUUAGAUGCAAAUACCUGCUAAGGGGAGAGUGAAAAAAUAAUUAUUUACAACAUAUACUGUAUAAAUGCCUUUAUCUUAAGUAUAGGAUGAUCAUAUUGCAGACUAAACCGAAGGUGAUGGAAGGGACCCUUAAGUAGAAGAGGCAUGUGUUGAACGCAGAUGAAAAUGUAAUGCUUGGGAACAAAUGUGCUGAUCUCAUAAUUGAAUCUAUUUUCAGCCUUUUCUAAGUUUCUGAUUAAAUAUGUGAUUUUUAAAAAUAUGUCUAUAUUAGAGUUUUUAAUUCUAUUAGGAUAAAAAGAGAGUCUGAUGGGAACACAUCUUCUUAAUUAUUAUGAAAGUGAGAAUGUGAGUCUAAUUGAUGAAAGUUCAAUUAGGAAAUGUGUUCUGUCUUGAUUUAUGCAUAUCUGGCCCUAAAUUAUCAGAAAUUGACAGAAUGGCAGGUUUGAAGGAGCUGAAGCCCCAGUCUGUCUCCUGCAAGAUCUUGCUUCAUCAGACAUCCCCUUUCUCUGGUAUCUUCUGUUUCUUCUAGGGUAUACUCCCCUAAAAAAGUCAAGUGCUGGACCAGCUUUCCCCUUAUACUACUGUCCCAUCUUUCACUUCAUUGCCAAACUUCUGGAAAGAAUAUUCUAGCCUAUCCUCGUCUCCAGUGCAUUCAUUCCUCCAACCCAUUCCAGUAUGGAGCUCAUUACUGGCCAAAUCUAGUGGCUCAUUUCCAUCUCAUUCUGUUUGAUCUCUUCCCCAGCAUUCAACAAUUUUGACCAUCGUCUUCUUGAAAGUCUUGGUUUCUGUAUUCCUGCACCAUCUUGAUUGUUCCUUUCCAGUCUCCACUACCUCUGUCUUUUCCUUAAAUGUAAAUAUGUCUUCACUCUCAUCCCUCUUCUCUUCUCAUCUUAUUAACUUUGCCUUGAUGGUUUCGUUUAGUUUAAAGUCGUCACUGCUAUGUAGAUGACUUCUAAAUCUAACCCUGAUAUUGUCCUUGAGUGAGUCCAAUGAGUCUAACCCUCAAAUUCCUUCCUCUGGGAGUCUGAGAAUCAUGAGCUCAUCUGGCGCAGUGGCUCACGCCUGUAAUCCCAGCACUUUGGGAGGCCGAGGAGGAUGGAUCACUUGAGGUCAGGAGUUCGAGACCAUCCUGGCCAACAUGGUGAAACCCUGUCCUACUAAAAAUAUAAAAAUAUUAGCUGGGUGUAGUGCUGGGCACCUGUAAUCCCAGCUACUCAGGAGUCUGAGGCAGGACAAUCGCUUGAACCCGGGAGGCAGAGGUUGCAGUGAGCUGAGAUCGUGCCAUUGUACUCCAGCCUGGGUGACAAAAGCAAAGCUCCAUCUCAAAAAAAAAAAAAAAAAAAAAAAGUAGAAUCACAAACUUCUUGUUGCCCUGACCUCUUUGCAGUUCAUGAAACCUACCUUUCAUCCUAUAUGUCCUGCAAGUUUGAGGAUCCCCAGUUGUUUAGGUUUGAUAACUUGAAGUCAGCUUUUCAGUUCCCCCCCUGCUAUUCCUCCCAUAGGCACAUCAAUUCUGAAUCCUGUAAGUUCUACUUAGUAGCAACACCCAGCUAUUUCCUCUCUUUUCUACUUAUGCUUCCUACCUUAAUCCAUGCUUCCAAACUGGCUUCCUUUCUUUCAGUUUCUUCCCCUUCCAGCUAAUCCUACACAAUGCUGCCAGUUGUUGUUUGUUUUGUUUUUAAAUAUGAUCAUGUUACUGUAUCAUCCUCUACCCCCCAAAAAACAAACCCCCAGUUACUUUUCAUAGCUUGUGCCCUACACUGCAGCUGCACAGGGCUGCCCUAUGCUCUUCUAGCACACACAGUACUUUCUUGGUUCAGAUUUUGCUGUCCCCUUUACCUGCAGUCCCCUCGUCUCUUGCUUACCCAUCUUCCACACACUUAGCCUUCAACAUCUUAAUCUGUCCUGUGUCCUUUUCCAGGCCAUAUGUGUGUGCCCCCAGUGAGAGUUCAUCUUACCGCUCAAUUGUUAGUCUUUGCAAGUUCCUCUAUCAGAGCACUUAUCUCAGUGUGCCUUAUGGAAUAAUUUUGUCAUAACUACCUCCUACCUCCCCCUACCACUGCCUGAUAAAUUAUGAGCUUAUCAAGGCAGGGAUCAGCCUUUAUUUCUCUCUCUACUGUCAGCACAGUGACAUCUGCAUGGGAGUUUUGUAAUGAUGGCUUUCUUCUUGAACUCGGGUUAGUAGAAAGGAAGGAAAAAUCACUAUAUGGAAACAAAUGAGAUGGAUGUUUCUGAGUAUUACAAAUCUAACACCAAAACCUAGAAAUCUCUGUUGCUGUUAUUGGAGUCAUCCACAGAGGGCUUGAUUUCUCAAGUCUGUGGUACUUGGCCAUAUUUUUCAUACCUGUGCUGAGAAUCCCUGCUUCUUGUUUUAGGAAGUCAAUAAAGUAAGAAACUGCCAAAAAAAAAAAAAAAAAAGUCAACUGAAUUGCUCAUAUGAAGUUUUGGAAGGUGACAUUAUCUUAGGUUUUAAUCACUGAAAGUCAUCCUUAAAAAAAGUUUGCCAGUCACCAAUACAAUGCAAGAUACAGAUUGAAACAGAUCAGCCCUUGACCCUGCUUUUGGAAUAGCAGUCCCUGAUAUUCAAGUCCACAUGUGCAACUGUUUCAUCAGUCAAGUUCAUUUCAUGUCUUGUGUUGGGUGGUGUCAGGAUGCAGUGGGGGCAGUCAAGGAUUUAGUAGUGUGUAGGAUGAGUGAUACCUAGUCCCAUUGAGGGAUGUGACAGUCAAACAGUAGUGAUGUGACAAAUAUGUUUAGCCCCAACAUAAGAUAGUAUACAUUCAUUUGUGCAAGAGAAACGCAAAGGAAAUCCACGGGGGACUCACAGGAAGAAGAGACCACAUCUAACCAAAAUUGGAAAGGCCUACAUGGAAUUGAUAGUUGUUAGUAUAGGGCCUUGAAGAAUGGAUUUAAUUUCCAGUGAAGGACUUCUGAGGUCUGGGGCUUGAGUGAUGAGGGUGGGGCACUGUCCACAGAGUAGGGAAGUCAGAAAAAGAUUUUAUUUGCAGAAACAGGUGGAAGAAAGGGGAAGGGGGAGGAACAAUGAGUUCUGUUUUGGACACAUAGCAUUUCAUGUAUUUUGACAGAAUUGACAGCAAGCCACUGAAGGCCUGCCCCUCAGUAAAGAGUCUAGAGAUAUAGAUUUGGAAUAGUGGUUCUUAAGUCAUUUGAAGUUAUGGGCUCCUUUGAGAAUACGAUGUAAAUUAUAGUUUCUUUUCCCCUCAAACAUGCAGUCAUGUACAAAACCUUACCUAAAAUUUUAGAGGACUUCUGGCCCCUCUGAAGCCCCUUUGUAGGGCCCUGGUAAAGUAAUCCUGGUAUGUAAUAGAGAAGUCCUGAACCAGAAUCUUGGGAGAGGCCAUCUUUUAGGGAGUGAAGAUAGGAAAGGAGCCAGAAAACGGAAUGGUUACAGAGGCGAGGGAAGAGCCUGGAAAGGAUUAACAGGAUGUCAUGGGUGUCAGUGCUGGGAGAGCUGGGGAGAUGGAUCACAAGCUCCCUAGGGACCUGACCCUAACUGACCUGCUUAAAGUCGGGACCUCCUUUUAUUAUCUUUGCAACUCUAGUGCCUAGUCCAGUGCCUGGCAUACGUUUUUGUUUUUUGGGGUUUUUUUUCUUUUUGAGCCUUUAUAAAUCUCAGAAAAUGAUCUCGGGGUGACGGGGACAAACACCAGUUUGCAGGUGUUUAAAGGAAGCAUAGUUGGUUUAAAAAAGAGUGGCAGGCAUGUUGAGGGAAGAAAGUUUUUACCUUAGAAUUUGAAAAAGGAAAAUGAAUAUAUUUGUGGAAAGAAAUCUUGCCUCUUUUCAAGGCAAGAGAGAGAAGGGAUCUUUUCUUGAGCAGGAUCCUGAAGAAGGCAGAGGGGGAUGGGAUCCAGCCCAGUUUGUGGGGCAGUUUGGGAAAGGAGAAGGGACCAUUAUUUCUGUGAGACAGGAGGGGAAGAAAAGUUUCCAAACUGUCACAGUGGGGAAUGUGGGAGUGUGCCAAAAAGGGCUUUCCUAGGAGGUAACAUAAGCCUGAUUGCCUUGAACAAUACAAAGGGCCCCUGCUUGAAAAAGAUCACUUUGUUAAUAUUAUUGGAACUGUUCAGCCAGCUGCAGAUUAUCUUAGUGAUUUUUAUUGGCAUUUGAAGUCAGAAGUGAACUUGCUGUUGCAUCUAUGAAAUGGUGUCUGGAGGCCAAGCAAGCUGGGUCCUGACUCCGGCCAGGUCAUGAAUACACCAUGAGUGGGCUUUUUCAUUUCAGACCACCCCUUUGGCUCUCUCUGGCCUCCUGUCCCAUUAGUAUUUUCACCACUCAGUGUUUUCAAGUCACGACUUAACACUUUGAAUUGAACUUGAGCUGUUCAGCAACAGAGUUCACCCCAAACCAUUAACUUCAUUGUUUCUGUGUUAUGUCAAUCUGGUAAGAUGCGCACUUUUUUUAGUAACAUUUCUAUUUUGGCCAAAAAUAGAAAUUUAUUCAUUUAUUUUCUUUUUAAAAAUCUAUUUGCUUUGCUUUUCAAACACUAGAAAUUGUACUGAAUUCUCAUAAAUUGCAUGAAGCUCAAUACUAGUUCUAGGUAAAUGAUAUAUUUUAAUAAAUGUCAGUGUUUCUGAUAGUAUGGCGAUUUUUUUAAGGCAGAAAUUAAAAUCAUGUAUAACUGAACAGAGCCUGAUAGUGCUACAGAAAGAUAAAGAGUUUGAUUGUUGGGGUGAUAAGUUCAAUGGCAAAGUUGUUCUUUUGUUGAUUUUCUUUAUUGUUUGCUCAUUUUUUACUCAGAUGGGAUAAUCAGAGAUAAUACACAUAUUAGAUGAGAGUUUUUUAAACUGUCAAUCCUAACCUAUUAAUGAGUCAUAAAAUCAAUUCACUAGGUUGCAGCCAGCAUUUUAAAAUAGAAUAGAAUAGAAUAAGAGCAUAACAUAAUAUGGAUAAGUGUGGCUACGUGAAACAUUUCUCUCCGGUGUAUGUGUGUAUUGGGUCAUGGUGUUGAAGUGCAUUGCUUACCGUUAAUCGUGGUCCAAAAAGUUUGAAAAACACCAUUUUAGGUAAUGGUAGAAUAUGUAGAAUAAACUGCACUUUAAGUUAUUGUAGGCGUGAAUAUAGUCACUUAAAUCUGCCUUUAUAGCAGUAGGCGCACAUGGAUUUUCUUGAAUUUUAAGUGAAGGUUUAGAGUUUAUGAAUAAACUUGUGGGAUAUAGACUCACACAAAGGAAGGCUAGGGCUAGAAGAAAUGAAGCCUGAGACCUGGGUGCCAGGCUCAUAGCAGCCACUGAUGGGGAGACCCUGUGAGGGGACACGUUUGCAGAGCCUUUCUGGUGUGUGGUAACAAGCAUGUGCCAUUGGAGUCCAGUGGUCUAUGUCUGAAUCCAGCUCAGUCACUUACCUGCUUGGUGACCUUGGAAGUCACAUAAUGUUUAUGUGCUUCUGUGUUCUCAUCUGUAAUGGAGAUAAUAACAGUCUCUACCCCGUUGGGGUUUUGUGAGGAUUAAAUGUAAAGUGCUUACGACGCUGCCUGGCACGCAGUAAGUACCCAAUAAAUGUCAGUUCUGUUCUUAGUGUGCCGUUUUCCCAGCAGGUGUAGAGAAUAAGGAUGACUACCCAGCACACUUUUGCCCAAGACUAUUAAUAAAGUAAUCGUGAUAACAUGUGGGGCACUUUAAGCUCUUUCAAAGAAAGAUGCUAUAUAUAGAUUAGUAUUCUUAUUAACAAACCAUUGGUUGUACCUUGAGAAAAGACUCUUUGAAAGUCAGAGCAUAAUAUCCAGAAAGCAUGUGACCUAGAAGGGUGAGAUACGGGGGGCAGUGAUAUGUAUGAAAAGAAUUCUUUAGAAAUGGUUUUCCAUGUUUUUCUUUCCAUCUUUUGACCCUGCUCAGGCUUACUGCUUUUAGGGAAACAUGGCUCAUUCAGGUUUUUGUUUUUGCACUUGCCGCUUUCCUUUCACAUUCUGCAUGAAGCUCUUUCGCAUCAAAAUAUUUCUGUUAUUCUGUGAACUGAUUAGCAGUCAUAUAGUUGCGAAAUUUUUGUUUUCGUGUGUGUGGUGGGAGAUAUUUGACCUUCUUAUGUCAGUCAGAAAAGACACAGGUGAGGUAACUUGCUCUUGGUAACUCUAAUUUCAGGAGAGAAGCAGCUGGGUUGCACAGCCUUUGCUGUGGAGACCAGCAGCCUUCUGAGGACUGCUGGUGUAGUACAUUAGAUUGCAUGCAAAGGAUGGAAGCAAGGUCUUCCAGACAGCAGCACCUUUGUGAGCAGGGCUCAUCAGCAUUUGCAGGUGUUUGUUACAGCCGCCUUUGGUUUUCAUAGUCUUUGCUGCUUAUUUCUUUUUGCCUAGCUUUGGUGAACCACAUCAAGCCCUGCCGUGUGGCUUAAACACUACCAUAUCUACCCCAUGUCCUCUCUUGCUCUACUCCAGUUGUGCUUACUUGUAAAAAGAUUUUCAUAAAAGUUAGUAGAGUGCGUUAUGGAGGUAUAUAUCUUUUAUGAUCAUUUGAAUGACAGGUAUAAAUGAUCCUAUGAAUGGAGAAUUAACAUAGGAUUUUUUUGUUAUUGUUGUUUUUGUUUUUUGAGACGGAGUCUUGCUCUGUCACCCAGGCUGGAGUGCAGUGGCAUGAUCUCGGCUCACUGCAACCUUCGCCUCCCCAGUUGAAGCGCUUCUCCUGCCUCAGCCUCCUGAGUAGCUGGGACUACAGGUGCUCACCACCACGCCCGACUAAUUUUUGUAUUUUUAGUAGAGACGGGGUUUCACCAUGUUAAGAUGGUCUCAAUCUCUUGACCUUGUGAUCCGCCCGCCUCAGCCUCCCAAAGUGCUGGGAUUACAGGUGUGAGCCACUGCGUCCAGCCAACAUAGGAUGUUUUAUUUUGUGCCUCAGAAAUGUGGAAAUUUUUAUAAAUUGCUUUGCAAUUUUAAACGAGGCUUAAAUUUAGUGGACCCUUACUUUCUGGGCUGAUUAUGGAAUUAAUAGAUAAAAAGAAACAACUCAUUUUCAGAGGGACACUGAAAUGAAGUACACACACACAUGCUUUUAGCCUAGAUGUGGCCUAAUGACUAAAAGUUAUGUCUUAGUUAUCUGUUUCCUUUUUGGGCAGGACUGUUUUUUCUUGAAUCAACAGUAAACUUGGCAAAUUGACACACUAGUUAUGCUUUUAAGUCUCCUUCCUUCCUGCCUCCUCUAAGACUUGGUCCUCUAUUCUCGUUGAUCUCUCUGUCUCCACCACCUUCUCCCUCUCAGCCUUGAAAUGUGCUUGGUUCUUCUCCCUAUUGCCUGUCCUCUGGAACUGACAUUUCACCUGGUCUCCUGUAGCAUUGUUGUCUAUGGUCAGAAGCGUAGAAUUCCCCGCUCGCAUCCAUUCACUCCAUAACUCAUUGCAAUCAGUCGUCUAGCCCGCUCACUGGAGUGGAAUGAUUCUUCUGAAAAUGACCGAAGACCCUACAAGUUAGAAAACUUGGUAGUCUGUUAGACCAUAUGCCUUUCAACUGCACCAUCGUUUGACUGUCAACUAUCCCACCCCUUCCUUGCAAAGUGGUGCUUUUAAAAUAUUGAGUAGAUACAAGAGGAUAUUUAUAAAAUAUGUAUAAAAUCUAAAGAAUGCUGAUUGAUGGAACUUUCCUUUGUCUCUCCUGAGAUGUAAGCUGGGUAAUUUCUUCAGUUUUAUCUUCUACUUCGGCUGUGCCUGAUCUGAGUUUUUGUUUGCUAAAAUUUCCAUUGUUAUGUUUUUUUAAUUAUAAAAGUUCUAUUUGAUUGUUUUUCAGAUCUGUUUGGCCAUUAUUUAUAAUCUCUUCUUCUGUGCUCAGAUUUCUCAUCCUCUUUUUGACUUCCGAAAGCACAUUAAAUGUAAUUUAUAAUAUGCAUCUGAUGAUUACAAUACCCGAAGUCUUUGUGGACUUUUCUACCACAGGUGUGUGUGUUUGCUGGCUCAUGGCACUUUGUUUCUGAUGUGGGUGUGUCUUGUGAUUAUUGCCUGCAAAUUCCUCUUCCUUGGAAGUUUAUCUGUGGGAAUACUCUGAGCAUAUGACUGAAGGCAAUUUUACCAAGAGAGGAUUUGUGUUUCUUUCUGCCAGGCAUCUUGAAGCAUGACUGGUUUGGGACGCUUAUGAAUUAAAUUCUCAGGUUGGAUGUUUUUGGGACCAUCCAAGUUUUGUGAGUUUCGUCCACAUACUACUUAAGGGCUGACUUGUGACUACAAAUUUCUAGUGGGGGAUGGUGGCAGGGAUUUGUUUCCUCCCUUGCUUAGCACCAAUAAUCUAGACAGGAAGGUUCUCUUGAAGUCCCCAGGUGGUCCUUUCCCAUGCAUCCUUCCCCUGAGUGUAGCACUUGGGAGGUUUCCUCAUUUUGGUUUGGCCAGGUCUUCAGGCCCUAUCUCCUGUGCCCCAAGAGGCCAUGAAAACCAGUUCUGGAAGUGGCCUGAAAGUGAAAGCCAGUGUGUUCCUCUUGCUGUCUGCAUUCCUGUUUGCAGUUAGUUUUUGGCUUCUGAGUAAAAAAGUCUCUGUUAUAUCCAGCAUUUUUAGGUGUUUUCAGCAGAAGUCCCAUUAUGGUAUAAAGACCAUCACAUUUGCAGACACCUCUCCCUCUUUUUUUUGAAACCUAACUUUCCCCAUAGCUUCUGAGAUCUAAGUCCUCUGCCUCUCACUUCUUUUCUGGCUCCUCUGCAUCCUUCUACCAUCUAGACAUGGGUUUUCUACAAAAGUCUGUCCUUGCUCUGAAUUAUGCCCUGGGCAAACUCAUGUCCACGAACAGUGCCUUUCUAAGCAUGGCUUCCAAAUAUAAAGCAUGGCUUUAUAUUUCCCUGUAGCUGUUAUAGAACUUCAAGCAACACCAAAAGAUCUGUUUAAAAUGACUCUCAUAUGCCCCAGAAACCCACUCCUCUGUGUUCCCAGUUACUCUUAAUGAUAUCAUUGUCCUCUUGUUCAUUCAAAUUUGAACAUUCGAAAUCAAGGCCAUCAGAGGUUUUCAUUUCUUCCUUUUCUUGUUUUCUUUUUUUUUUUUUGAGACAGGGUCUUGCUCUGUCACCCAGGGUGGAGUGCAGUGGUGUGAUCACAGCUCACCGCAGCCCGCAGGUGCAUGACUCUACACCUGGCUAAUUUAUUUUUCUUUUCUUUUAGAUGGUGUCUCACUGUGUUGCCCAGGCUGACCUCAAACUCUUGACUUCAAGAAAUCCUACUGCCUCUGCCCCCUAAAGUGCUGGGAUUACAGGCAUGAGCCACCAUACCUGGCCCCUGUUUCGUAGCAUGUACUAAAUCCAGGGGAUUCUGCCUCCCCAGCCUGACUUAAUUCAUAUCUUCAUCUCCUCUCUUCUAAACUGUUGGAACAUUGUUAGGAGGUCUUUCUACCUCCAUUCUGUCUCCUAUCCCUUGCCCGCAAACUUCAACCAGUUCCUCCCUCUCUGUCAGUGUGAAGGCAGACCUCUGUCUCUUUCACAGUGUGGCCCACCUCUCUCCGUUGUUUGUUAUCCGUCUUCACUCAGUGGAGUUGAGUGUAGACUGAGAUGUUCGCCAGUGGCCAUAUAUUCUCUGAGUUUGGCUGCCAUUUGUGCCUUUUUGUUGUCGUCUUGUCCAGAGUUGUCUUAUCCUUCCAGGGUAGUUCAGAUACCAACAACGUCCCUCCAAGCCCCAUCUGUCAAGAAGUUAUCUGGGCAUUCUCUGGGCCUCAUAGUACUUUCUCUCUCCCACCUGUGGCACUUGCUGCUAUCCUCUCUAUAUGCCCUCCUCAUCUCUCUCCUUUGGAUGACUUCCAACUCCUUAAAAACAGAGGCUGUGUCUUCCUUGCCUUUUUCUCCACUUCAUACCUUGUUCAUAGUAGAGCCUCAGUAAAUGUUUAUCGAGUGAAUAUACUAAUGUAAACAGAGCGAAUUAAUCGGAAUCAGUAGCAACCAAGACAUCAAUGAGAAUAUUCUGCUUUUUAGAAAUAGCAUUUAUUCAAUAAAUAUUUACUUUUUAAUUUAAGUUGUAAAUAGGUAAUAUAUGUUCAUGAUUGACAAUUCAGGAACUGUAAAAGGGUAUACAGGAAAAAAUCUCCCUCCCGGCACACUUCAGCUACCUCAUUGCCCUCCUCAUAGACAACCCAGGUUUCAGUUUAUUGUGUCUCCACCCAGUGAUAGUUUAGGCCUAUACACUUAACUGAUUCACAUGCCUUCCCCCUUAACCCUAAUGGUAGAGAGCUAUAUACACUGUCAUGUACCUAUUUCCAUCCACCAAUAGACAUUGCCCAGUGAAUGUGCUUCUCCACCCUAUGAUCUUCAUUCCAUGUACUACCUUAAUUCCUCAUUGCCAUAUAUGGUAACGUAACACAGGUUUGAGGGAUUAGGACAUGGACAUCUUUGGGAAGACAUUCUUCUUCUUAUUUUUUUAAACAGAGUCUUGCUCUGUUGCCCAGGCUGGAGUGCAGUGGCACAAUCUCAGCUCACUGCAACCUCCGCCUCCCGGGUUCAAGCGAUUUUCGUGCCUCAGCCUCCCAAGUAGCUGAGAUUAUAGCGUGGGCCACCACACCCGGCUAAUUUUUAUAUUUUUAGUAGAGAUGGGGUUUCGCCAUGUUGGCCAGGCUGAUCUUGAACCCCUGACCUCAGAGGUGAUCUGCCCUCCUCAGCCUCCCAACAUGCUGGGAUUACAGGCAUGAGGCCCAGCCCUGGCUGGGAGGUCUUUAUUCUGCUUACCAUAGCAACCCAGUAUGUUUUCUGAUCUUUUAAUCUUUUUCAAUCUAAUAGGUGAAAAUGUAGCUUCCAGUUUUAUUUUGCAUUUAUCUUGUAUGAGUAAAAUUGAAUAUCUUUAGGUUUGAGCUAUUUGUAUUUGCAUUUCUCCAUUCUCUGUAUCUUCUACCUAUUUUUUGUUUGGAUGUUUGGUCUUUUUCUUGUUAGUUGUACGUACUUUUUGUGUAAUAGCUAUAGUGAUGUUUAAUAUGAGUGACUAAUAUUUUUCCUGUAUGUUUUUUGACUUUAUGAUGGAUUUUGCUAUGGAGACUUGUUUUCUAUUUAUUUGGUAGCAUUUGAGAGUCUGUGUUGAGGGGCUCUAAAACCACCCCCACGUGUGGUGAUUCGAUAACAGGACUCACUGGACUCAUAUUGUACUCACAGGUAUGGCUUAUUACAGCACAAGGAUACAAAACAAAACCAGCAAAGAGAAAAGGCACAUAGGUUGAAAUUCGGGGGAAACCAGGCACAGGCUUCCAGAGUUCUUGUCCAGUGGAAUCAAACAGGAUGCACUUAAUUCCUCCAGCAAUGAGUUGUGCAGCACAUAUGAGAUGUUGCCCACCUGGGAAGUUCAUUGGAGACUUUGUGUCCACAGUGUUUAUUGGGGCUGGCCAUGUAAGCACCCACUGCCUAGCACAAGCAAAAUUCCAGGCUUCCAGAAGAAAAGCAGGAGUUCAGUGUAAACCACAUUGUUUAUACAAACAGUUUGGGCACAGUGAACCAAUCUUACCAGUGAGGGAAUGGUGAGAACUCUGCUGAAAUCCAGAUUACCAAGUGUCUGGCAAGGGCCAACCAUGUAUGCAGGCCUUUCUAAGGAGGGCAGCCUCAGGCCUGCCAUGUUAAUUCUUCUGCACACUUUUCUUUUAUAGCUUCUGAGCUUUCUAUCCCAAUUAGGAAGAUCUUCCCUACUCAGACUUCUAAGGAAUUAUCUCAGCCAGGCGUGGUGAGUCACGCCUUGCAAUCCCAGCACUUUGGGAAGUCGAGGCAGGCAGAUCACCUGAGGUCAGGGAUUCGAGACCAGCCUGGCCAACAUGGUGAAACCCUGUCUCUACUAAAAAUACAAAAAUUAGCUGGGUGUGGUGGCACAUGCCUAUAAUUCCAGCUACUCACGAGGCUGAGGCACGAGAAUUGCUUGAACCUGGGAGGCAGAAUUUGUAGUGAGCCGAGAUUGCUCCACUGCACUCCAGCCGGGGCGACAGAAUGAGUGAGACUCCAUCUCCAAAAAAAAAAAAAAAAAAAAAAAAACAAAUAAAAUAAAUUAUCUCAUAUUCCUCUAGUAAUUUGGUUUCUUCCUUAAGAUUUAAGUAUUUCAUCUAUUUGGAAUUUAUUUGGAGUUAAAGUAUAAGAUAUGAAUCCAACUCUUUCUUCCCCUCUUGUUGCAAUAUCAUUUGUUGACUAGUUUGCUGAUUUGAAGUACUGUCCUUAUCUCACACUAAAUUCCUCUGCAUGUUUGAUUUUAUUUCUAAGAGGUUCUCGUUGCAUUAAUUAUUCUAUUCAUGCACCAGGUGUGCUCUUUUAACUAUUGAAGCUGUAUAAGAUGUUGCACUGUAUGGUAGAACGAGCCUCCCCUUGUUCCUCUUCUUUUUCUUUUCCUUUCUAUUGUUGCUUAAGCAAUUACAGAAUGCUACAUUAUGGCUGUGCUCAGGGAUCUAGAGCUGAUACCCACUUCCUGUUCCCAAGGAGUGCUGUUUUCCUGGGUAAUGCAAACAAACAGAUGCAUAUGAUACAGUGGUGCACAGGAUGUCACAGGAGCACAAAGGAGGGCUUCCUAGAGGAUUCAGAUUCUGCAAGAUGAGUAGGAGCAUUUGUCAGGCAGAAAUUGACAUGUCAUACUGAAGGAACAGUCUGUGGGCAUGCAAAGAGGCCGCACAGAUGCAGGCUGAACUCACAUGCAGUUUGGUGUCCGGGAGCACAGCGUGCAUGUGGGGGUACCAACAGGAGAUAGUGCUGGGGGCAGAGGAGGCUGGGUCAAAGAUUGCAGAGCCUAACAUUCCCCACUCAGAAUGUCUGCUUUUUAUCUGAAGGUGAAGGGAGCCAUUUAAUGGUUUUAAGCAGGAACGUGGCAUGAUUAAAUUUCCAUUUCAAAAAGAUUGCUGGGCUGCAGUGUGUGCAGAGUAGGUGGAGGGGACGGGAGUGGAGGAGAGAGGAAGACCAUUUCUGGGGAUUUUUGCUAGUCACCCCAGUCCUUGAUGAUGAGGGCUUGAAGUGGGGCAAUGGACAGGGACUCCAGAUGAUGCUUUUGAGAAAGAUUCAGAUGGUAAAAUCAGUAGAAUUUGGUGGUUGACUGAAUGUAGUUAUGAGGGAGGAUGGGAUGAUAGGGAAGAAUCCACCCUGGAUAACCAGACCGAUGGUGGGGCCAGUGGUUGAGAUGGGGAACAUAGGAGGGGAGUGAGGAAGAGGUGGCAAGUUCCAUUUUGGUUAUGUUGAGUUGAGAGUGUCUGUGAGACAGCCAGGCAGAGAUACCUAGGAGACAGAUGACCACAUAGAUCCAGAGCUCUGGCCUGGGGAGAGCUUUAUUUGGUACUCCUGGAUCACAUCCACAUCACAUCACUAGCAUUUUCAUAGAUGUGGCCAAAAUUGCCAGGAGAGAGAACUACAGUGAGAAGAGGGACAAUGUAUGAACCCUCAGAAAUCUCAGCCUUAAAUGAUUAUGAUAGUGGACAAGUUGUAAAGAAUAUUCUUUUUUCCAAAAUAGUUUCAAAUGACAUUUCAAAUGUACAUUUGUGGUCCUUUCGUGAACAAAUAAAUAGGUACGUUUAUAUAUGAAGACAAUGAUGACACAGGAAUAUCAAGCCAUUUCCCCCAGAGGUACUGAUUUAGUCAGUAGUAGAAAUAGGAUUAGGAGAACUGUUUAUGCAAACAGAAGUAUAAUUGGUAAUCUAUGUGCUAGCUGCUUUUGACCUGUUAUCUUUUGUCAGGUUUUUGGAAUAACUGCGUCAAAACUGAUAUAAAUGAACUUACUGUGUCAAGUCGUGUGAAAUAUACAGAAAGCAUUAUCUAGCAUUAGGGCAUUAGAAUUAUAAACUUUACCACAUAUCAGUACGUCCUAUGGUUCUUUAAAAUUUUAGGCUUUCCCCUCCAAUUUUAAUGAAAGCAUUUUUUUCUUACAUGAUCAAGUCUUGUUUCUAAAGUUUAAAAGAUGAAAAUGAGGUAAUUUUACAUUACUGUACCCUUAAAUGGUAGAUGGAAGCUUUUUAAAAAGAUGAGUGUCUUUAAUUUCAGAAAUCAAAUUCAAAAAAAAAAAAAGCUAGCUUCAAUUCCUGUUCAAACGUUGCAAAAUUUAAUCCAGAAAGAAGCAGUUGGGCCAGAUGCCGUGGCUCACGCCUGUAAGCCAAGCACUUUGAAAGGCCAAGGUGGGUAGAUUGCCUGAGCUCAGGAGUUCAAGGCCAGCCUGGGCAACAUGGUGAAACCCUGUGUCUACUAAAAUACAAAAAAAAAUUAGCUGGGCGUGGUGAUGUGUGCCUGUAGUCCCAGCUACUCUGGAGGCUGAGGCACGAGAAUUGCUUGAACCCAGGAGGCGGAGGUUGCAGUGAGCCAAGAUGGCACCACUGCACUCCAGCGUGGGCGAUAGAGCCAGGACUCUGUCUCAAAAACAAAAAGAAGCAGUUAGUAAGUGGUUCCCUGAAGUUUUAAGUUUAGGUAUUUGGAGACAUAGGUCAUUAAGAGUCAUCUUCCUGAAAAAUCACAUUCAUCAGUUGUGCCAUUGGGUGCUGUUAACAUCAUUUGAAAACACUUUUAAAUGUUCAUAGUUUAUCAAUUUAUUCCCCUGAUUAUGAGCUGGAGAGAGCCUAUGACAGUGACAGACAGCUGUCCGUCCUCAAAGGAAACUCAAGAAUUAACAUUUAUAGAUUCUGUUUAAAUAAACAAAAAAUCCAAUCUAGAUGUUUUAAGGAAAUCAGUGCAUCUUUAUAUAGGUGCCAUUUAAAAAUAAUGGCUAAUUAAGUGAAAGCUAAAAUCUGUUGUCAUUUCAGAGACUUUACCCCCACAAGUUACAAUGAUAAAUGUAGCUAAAUUAAAAUGACAAGUUAUAUUCCCUAUGUCAGAGCUGUUUUUAUCCCUGGUGUGAAAUCAGAGAGUUUCAUCUCAAGUUUGUCCUUUAACAUUUUUCAAAUGUUACAUUGUGCUAUUUUUAAUCCGGAAACAAUGCACAUGAUUGCUUUAAAAAAAAAAAGUCUCCAUGUACAGUAUCUCUUGACUAGUACGGAUCUAGUGAAUUGUGAAUUGAUGAAAUGCCCAAAUACUAAUAUAGAGCAAAAUUAAGGAAGACAUGACUUGCUCACUUGAGGAAGGUGAGGGUGGCCAUUUGAGAGUAUCUUCUGUCAGUUUCCUGAUUUUGAUAUUGUGCUAAAAGUUAUACAAGAUGUUAACACCUGGAGAGGCUGGCUGAAGAUUUACUUCUUGUGAAUCUAUAAUUAUUUCAAAAUAAUCUAAAACAAACUAAAGUAGCUCCCCAACAGCUUGACCACACAGAAUCCUUAGGCUACAUUCCUGAGAGUUCUGGUACAUCCCACAUGGCCCUUCUAGGACCAAGGAGGUAGAAAGUCACCCCCUAGAGAUUCUGAUUCAGUAGGGGUGAGGCAGGGCACAGGGCAUGGUUUAGCCUCUGGAAAAAGCAGCCCACUUCACCCCCAAUUCUGAGGCAGAGCCGUAGAUAAGGACCACACCCUAGAAGAAAGCCACGUAGGACUUGCUGAAGCAUCUACUGAAAGGUGAUGCUCAGCAAAACAUCUUCUCUGUCCUAAGACUUUGCUCAAUUGGGACUGAAUCGUUCUUGAAUUUUCCAUAGUCGAUGAAAUCAGUACUUGGACGUGUUCAUUGAGUAAGCUUUAUCAUUACCCAUUUAGCAAACAAGACGCGCUUGAUGGUUAUAGUGGAAAAUACUUGAGAGCCAGCUCUCUCCAUGUGAUUUAGAGUUCCCAAAUUAAGGGUCAAAAUUGACCCAAGGUUAUAUUUAAGAAUAAUAGUUGAAAGUGUCAACACAUUAAUAAAGUGUUAAAGAAUACAUUGUCUGGAAGAGAAAGUAAAUGACAGCUAAAAACCUCAAGACGUAUAACCUAUUCACUUCAGGUUUUAACAAUUUUGAAAUAGGAGCUUUAAUUAGGCUUGUAACAAGUUACCACUUGUAGGGGAUUUUAUGCUUUUUGAUAAUGAGGUACAGAUGAAUGUGUUUUGUUAUUGCUUUAUUUUUGUUUUUGUAAUAAUCCAACUUUAUGUUACUCUGAGAGCCUAUAUUCUCUUAAUCUUUAAGAAAAAAAGAAAAUAUAUCUGAAAAGUAGGUCCUCGUACUUUCAAGUUCAGAAAAUGGUGGUAUUGGCUCUUUCAGACUGCUCACUUCAAUUGAGCCAAGUAGCUUAUGGAAAACUUAGUUUUUAAAUAAAAACACCACAUAAACACUACCUAGUAAUGCUUUUUGAAAAAUGUUUUUCUGUGUUUGUAAGCUAAUUUAUUUGAAUGGUGAAAAUAUUGGUUUAAGCACCCAGUCUUUUCUACCCUAAGCUCCAAUUUAAUAUUAGAUGUGUUGCUAUGUGCUUCACGAGGAGAAAUAUUUGGCUGUUGUGCGAUUCAUAAUUCUUCCUGAAAUAUCUGGGGUCCAAGCCUGGCUCUUAGCAUCAAGAGUAAACUGGGAGUUGUUUUUGUCACCAAUUCUAAUAGACAUGUUUCGGGUUAAAGGAUACCAGUUAGUUGACUCAUUCUGGAUAUUAGUCAGAAUGUGAAGUAUCAUCAUAGAAGUGAUCUCAUCAGAGAGUCCAUCUGAUGUGUGGUUACCAUGGGGACAUUGUCUCAGUCUCAUACUAAUGACAAAAAAAAAUUGAUGUUGCUUCUGUUCAGGUUCUUUUAUAAAACAUAUUAAGGAAGUUAGGUAGAUAAUUUUUGUUUAGGCCAUAUAGCUUUGAUUUUCUGAUAACAAUUUUAUAAACUUAGAAAUUUUCAUGUAAGAUACAGGAAUACUGGAAGCAAAAAAAAGAAGGUGCUUUAACCUUAGGGAUUGAAAAAAUAGUAAUUUAGGUUGAAAAUGCUGCUUGAAAGUUAAUGCUGAUAGCAUUACUACACAUGAUGAUUUUUUCUGGAAGGAAAGCUUUAUCUGGGCCUUCAAUUUAGGAAUUUUUCUCUUUGGUUUUUAAAAGCUGCCAUAUUCACUUGAGCUUCAUGGGAAAGAUGCAAAUAACUAAAACAAAUGAACAAAAACCAUGUUGAGGUCAGGAACUUAUUUCAAGAAAGCAAGUUCUAGGUUUUCUUUUAAAGUGACAGUAGAGCCUUAGGCCUCAAACCAUCUACAACCAUGUUAACAGUACAUCACUCAAAUCAUUCAACAUUCCUGAAUGUUUACCUGUGCCAAGUACUGACCAGCGCAGUAUCAGAUGUUCACAGUAAUGAUAUAUUGCCAAGAGAAUGCUUAGGCAUGUCCCAUAUAUUCUGUUUAUGGAUAAAGGAGUGCACCAAACAUUUUAGUGCUAUUUUCGCCCAAAGUCCCUCUGUCUUUAAUUUAAACUUAACAGAAAUCACUUAUUUUUCCCAGUGGUACUGAAUAAUUAUGCAUUGCUGUGGAUUCAGUGUCAGGUUAAAGCCUCAGUGCAUCGCUUAGCUAGGUCAGCAUCAUUACCAGUGUGUGCUUAUCAUGCCAGCCAUCCAGAAUAAACAGCACUUGGGCCUAGCGCUGCCAGAGUUGAGACCUGCAGAGUGUGCUGCAUGCCUGGGAAAGUUUGAGAAGACAUUGUGGAGAGCAUGUUCUUGGGCAGUUUUCACCUUAAACCUCUUGCCAUUCACAUGCAGAAAACUGUUGCUGCUGAAAGAUGCUUUUCCAGAAAUACACUGUGUUGUAGGGGAGGGAACACUGGUGUUCAAAGUGAUUAGUCUGAUGACAGAGGAAAAUGGUUGGGGAGGGAGCUACAUAGAGGAAAAGUGCCCAGACGCAGCGCCUCCAGAGAAGAUGGUUGUACAGGGGCUGUGUGGGCCUUCAUGUCUUCAUUCGGUCAGCGAGCCUGUGUUCUGCCUCCCUCUGACCAGGCGCCAUUGUAGUUACUGGGGAUAAAGGAUGGGAAUGAAGCAAGUGUGUACUUUCAUGGAGCCCAUGUCCUAGGGGAGGGGAUAGUACAUAUGUACAGUGAACAAGUACAUAUGUAAUAUGUCAAAUGGUCAUAAGUGAUAGGGAAAAUCAGAUGGGAAUAGGGAGUGCUGUUGUGAGGGUAACAUGUUUUUUUGUAGGGUGUCGGAGAAGGUCUUACUGAUUAAGAUUAUUGGAUCAGAGAUGUGAGAGAAGACAAGAAGCCAUGAGGUAAACGAAUUCCAGGCAGAUGGAAUAGUAGCCGCAAAGGCCCUGAGAGUGGCAUGUGCUUGGUGCCUUUAGGGAGUGGCACAGGAGGCAGGUGUGACUUACGUGGAGCGAGUGAGUCUGAGAGCAGAGAUGUGGCGGGGGAGAUGGCCAGAUGGCAGACAGCUGCAUAAGCCAUUGGAAGGACUUCCACCUUUACUCCUCGCAAAGUGGAAAGCUACGGGAGGAUUUGGGGCAAGGAAAGGACUUGAUCUGACCUAUGACACUGUCACUCUGACUUGAGAAGUACAAAGAUGAAAGCAGGGGAGCAGUUAGGUUUUUAUAAUCAACCAAGUAAGAGAUGAUGGUGGCUUGGACCUGGGUGGUAGCCACGUGGUGACAAAGAUGAAUCCAAGGUUUUCAGCUCAAUCAGCUGGAAGUCAUGUACUGAAAUGGGGAGACUGUGGGAAGAGCAGGACUGGGUAGGGGGAGCCAAGAGUGUUUGGCUUUGGUUGUGUUAACUUGAGAGUUCUUCAGAUGCCUCUUAGGCAGUCUGGUGGGGUGGUAGAGUGGACACUUGGAUAGCCAAGUCUGGAAUUCAGAGGGGAUGCUGGAGAAUGAUAGGUCCUUACUAGUCACUAGAGUAUGGAUGGUAUUUGAAGCUAUCAAAUGUAUCAACAGCACGUUGAGGGUGAGUAUAUAUAGAGAAGAGGUGAGAGGUCUGAGUCCUGCCAUUUCACAGAAACCAGGGCAUUGAUUCAGAAUUCACAGAGAACAGUUAGCUCAGAGUUUUCUUAAUAUCCUAUCUUUUUAAAAAAUAAACAUGUCAUUGUUCCCUUUUGAGACAGUUGCACCGUUUAACAAUAAUUCCUGAAUUUUAUUUUUCUUCCUUUCCUUCUUUCUUUUUAGUGGCUUGUACCUGAUCAAUUGCUAAUACUGUUUAAAAUUGAUAGGCACUUUUUGGUCUGGUAAUCUGAUUUUUUUGUGGAACAUCAUUAAAAGAACAAUUGAGAGAUUUAUAGCCAUAGAAAAUUGAGGCUUCUAUUACUCAAGAUAGAAGUUAGCCCAUUAUUUGCAUUUUUAAAUGAAGAAAAGUUUAACGUGGAUGGAUGGACAGUUUACAAUCCAGUGGAAGAAUACAGGAGGCAGGGCUUGCCCAAUCACCAUUGGAGAAUAACUUUUAUUAAUAAGUGCUAUGAGCUCUGUGACACUUACCCUGCUCUUUUGGUGGUUCCGUAUCGUGCCUCAGAUGAUGACCUCCGGAGAGUUGCAACUUUUAGGUCCCGAAAUCGAAUUCCAGUGCUGUCAUGGAUUCAUCCAGAAAAUAAGACGGUCAUUGUGCGUUGCAGUCAGCCUCUUGUCGGUAUGAGUGGGAAACGAAAUAAAGAUGAUGAGAAAUAUCUCGAUGUUAUCAGGGAGACUAAUAAACAAAUUUCUAAACUCACCAUUUAUGAUGCAAGACCCAGCGUAAAUGCAGUGGCCAACAAGGCAACAGGAGGAGGAUAUGAAAGUGAUGAUGCAUAUCAUAACGCCGAACUUUUCUUCUUAGACAUUCAUAAUAUUCAUGUUAUGCGGGAAUCUUUAAAAAAAGUGAAGGACAUUGUUUAUCCUAAUGUAGAAGAAUCUCAUUGGUUGUCCAGUUUGGAGUCUACUCAUUGGUUAGAACAUAUCAAGCUCGUUUUGACAGGAGCCAUUCAAGUAGCAGACAAAGUUUCUUCAGGGAAGAGUUCAGUGCUUGUGCAUUGCAGUGACGGAUGGGACAGGACUGCUCAGCUGACAUCCUUGGCCAUGCUGAUGUUGGAUAGCUUCUAUAGGAGCAUUGAAGGGUUCGAAAUACUGGUACAAAAAGAAUGGAUAAGUUUUGGACAUAAAUUUGCAUCUCGAAUAGGUCAUGGUGAUAAAAACCACACCGAUGCUGACCGUUCUCCUAUUUUUCUCCAGUUUAUUGAUUGUGUGUGGCAAAUGUCAAAACAGUUCCCUACAGCUUUUGAAUUCAAUGAACAAUUUUUGAUUAUAAUUUUGGAUCAUCUGUAUAGUUGCCGAUUUGGUACUUUCUUAUUCAACUGUGAAUCUGCUCGAGAAAGACAGAAGGUUACAGAAAGGACUGUUUCUUUAUGGUCACUGAUAAACAGUAAUAAAGAAAAAUUCAAAAACCCCUUCUAUACUAAAGAAAUCAAUCGAGUUUUAUAUCCAGUUGCCAGUAUGCGUCACUUGGAACUCUGGGUGAAUUACUACAUUAGAUGGAACCCCAGGAUCAAGCAACAACAGCCGAAUCCAGUGGAGCAGCGUUACAUGGAGCUCUUAGCCUUACGCGACGAAUACAUAAAGCGGCUUGAGGAACUGCAGCUCGCCAACUCUGCCAAGCUUUCUGAUCCCCCAACUUCACCUUCCAGUCCUUCGCAAAUGAUGCCCCAUGUGCAAACUCACUUCUGAGGGGGGACCCUGGCACCGCAUUAGAGCUCGAAAUAAAGGCGAUAGCUGACUUUCAUUUGGGGCAUUUGUAAAAAGUAGAUUAAAAUAUUUGCCUCCAUGUAGAACUUGAACUAACAUAAUCUUAAACUCUUGAAUAUGUGCCUUCUAGAAUACAUAUUACAAGAAAACUACAGGGUCCACACGGCAAUCAGAAGAAAGGAGCUGAGAUGAGGUUUUGGAAAACCCUGACACCUUUAAAAAGCAGUUUUUGAAAGACAAAAUUUAGAUUUAAUUUACGUCUUGAGAAAUACUAUAUAUACAAUAUAUAUUUUGUGGGCUUAAUUGAAACAACAUUAUUUUAAAAUCAAAGGGGAUAUAUGUUUGUGGAAUGGAUUUUCCUGAAGCUGCUUAACAGUUGCUUUGGAUUCUCUAAGAUGAAUCCAAAUGUGAAAGAUGCAUGUUACUGCCAAAACCAAAUUGAGCUCAGCUUCCUAGGCAUUACCCAAAAGCAAGGUGUUUAAGUAAUUGCCAGCUUUUAUACCAUCAUGAGUGGUGACUUAAGGAGAAAUAGCUGUAUAGAUGAGUUUUUCAUUAUUUGGAAAUUUAGGGGUAGAAAAUGUUUUCCCCUAAUUUUCCAGAGAAGCCUAUUUUUAUAUUUUUAAAAAACUGACAGGGCCCAGUUAAAUAUGAUUUGCAUUUUUUAAAUUUGCCAGUUUUAUUUUCUAAAUUCUUUCAUGAGCUUGCCUAAAAUUCGGAAUGGUUUUCGGGUUGUGGCAAACCCCAAAGAGAGCACUGUCCAAGGAUGUCGGGAGCAUCCUGCUGCUUAGGGGAAUGUUUUCGCAAAUGUUGCUCUAGUCAGUCCAGCUCAUCUGCCAAAAUGUAGGGCUACCGUCUUGGAUGCAUGAGCUAUUGCUAGAGCAUCAUCCUUAGAAAUCAGUGCCCCAGAUGUACAUGUGUUGAGCGUAUUCUUGAAAGUAUUGUGUUUAUGCAUUUCAAUUUCAAUGGUGUUGGCUUCCCCUCCCCACCCCACGCGUGCAUAAAAACUGGUUCUACAAAUUUUUACUUGAAGUACCAGGCCGUUUGCUUUUUCAGGUUGUUUUGUUUUAUAGUAUUAAGUGAAAUUUUAAAUGCACAGUUCUAUUUGCUAUCUGAACUAAUUCAUUUAUUAAGUAUAUUUGUAAAAGCUAAGGCUCGAGUUAAAACAAUGAAGUGUUUUACAAUGAUUUGUAAAGGACUAUUUAUAACUAAUAUGGUUUUGUUUUCAAUGAAUUAAGAAAGAUUAAAUAUAUCUUUGUAAAUUAUUUUAUGUCAUAGUUUAAUUGGUCUACCAAGUAAGACAUCUCAAAUACAGUAGUAUAAUGUAUGAAUUUUGUAAGUAUAAGAAAUUUUAUUAGACAUUCUCUUACUUUUUGUAAAUGCUGUAAAUAUUUCAUAAAUUAACAAAGUGUCACUCCAUAAAAAGAAAGCUAAUACUAAUAGCCUAAAAGAUUUUGUGAAAUUUCAUGAAAACUUUUUAAUGGCAAUAAUGACUAAAGACCUGCUGUAAUAAAUGUAUUAACUGAAACCUAA